CUCUUUCCUGCGUCCGCCCCCAGCUACCCACCCUCGCUGUCCGUGCGGGGUCGAGGCUGGGACCCGGGUGAACAGGGACUGCUCUAAGGCGUCACUGUGACGGCGUUAAUCAAAAUAAAUCAUUAAUCAAAUGCAGUGUGCGGAGUUCGUCUUCCCCGUGUCUUCCCGCAGAUCCCGUAGUGGAGGCUGGAGCCGCAGGGGGUCGCUGCCGCCCACAGAAAGAGGAGAAUGCCAGGCAUCCUCGGAGGGAGGCCUCCAUCUGUGUUUUUUGAAAAAAGGUUAACAUCUAGACAUAGUUAACUGAGCAUACAUAGCUUUCCACUCGUUUUUGCUUUAAAAUACACUCAAAAAGCAGAAAGCCUGCAGGAUGCUUCUUGGGCUCUUGUUGCGGACGAAUAGGCUCGGCUAUUCUUGUUGCUGAAGAAUAGCCUCUGCUGGUGUGGAGGAGGGAAGCUGCCCCCGGAUUAGACAGCAGGAUGACAAGGAAAAAGGCAGAUGCGCCCUCUCCUGGUAUCUCCGAAGGAUUCUGCUUCGCUGUCUGGACCUCCUGCUGCCUGGCCAAGCCUGACUCUCAACCCUGCCCCUGAGGCUAACCCCAAGAGCAGGGCAGAGAAGCAAGCAAGUCAGCGACUGCCCCAGACCCAAUUCCGGGCCCUCGAGUUGGUGUGGUGUAGGAGGGGCAGAUGAGGCUAGAGGCUGCUUUAUAAGGAGCAGAAAAGACGGUGUCACAGCUGUACCCUGGGAUCGGCAGAAAAGGGUCCCCCCGGGGCCUGUAAGGGGUGCCUGCGUAACAGGUGACUUGAAUUUCAAGUGAUUAUCAUAUAAAUGGAGGAUUAGAAAAGAGACACCAACUCUGGAACCAGUUCAAUGGAAUUCUUCAAGAGACUGUAACUUAGUGCUUACAAAGACUUGGAAUGAUCUACACUGCAUGGUGUACCUGUUAGAGGAGGUGACAUCAAAGCUUUAGGUACUGAGAGAGGAUACUUCCUACUGUGGAAGGGAAGAAAAGAAAAAAGCAAAGCUACUUCUUGGAAGAGCAGUGGAGAGAAAAAUAUUGUUUCUUUUUCUUGGGAAAUUGGCAGAGGCAUGCUGAAGAAAUCAGCUACAGCUGUUCUCCACACCUGGAUAAAUUUUUAAUAAGAACUUAACACACCCGCCCUCCAGAAAGGGUGGUCUGAGGUGUCGAUGGUGUUGUCUCUCCCAGGGCUCUUCUGGGCAGCCUUCUCUGUGACCUGGAGAGCGAAGAGUCUAUUUCCAUCACAUUUCAGCUGCCAAACUCCCCUUUAAACGAUGGAUGAAAAUUAUAACCUCUUGCCUCACGGAGUCAAUUUCCAAGAUGCCAUCUUCCCAGACACUCAAGAGAACAGAAGGAUGUUUUCUAGCCUUUUCCAGUUUUCAAACUGUUCGCAAGGGCAGCAGCUGGCGACUUUCUCCAGUGACUGGGAAAUCCAGGAAGACAGUAGGCUCAUGUGCUCCUCGGUGCAGAAGGCCUUGUUUGAGGAGGAGGACCACGUCAAGAAACUGCAGCAGAAAGUGGCCACCCUGGAGAAGCGCAACCGGCAGCUCCGGGAGCGAGUGAAGAAGGUCAAGAGGUCCUUGCGGCAGGCGCGUAAGAAGGGCCGCCACCUGGAGCUGGCGAACCAGAAACUCAGUGAGAAGCUGGCGGCGGGCGCGCUGCCGCACAUCAAUGCCCGGGGGCCCGUGCGCCCCCCCUACCUGCGGGGGUAACGGGCCUGGGGGCUGCCAGGUGUGCAGGGCCAAUCCUGACGGUAAUUGAGAAUGAGUGAGGUUUCGUACAUGCAGCUAUUUCAAGGGUUGUAAGAGUUUUUGUUUUUAAUCACGCAUUUGGUAGAGUCUAAAUGGAUAAAAUGCAAGGCUUGCUUUCCCCUUGGGUGCUGGCCUCAAUGUCAGACCCCACGCGCUGCCCCUUCCUGGCCUGACCCCAGACGCAGUGCCUGGCAGUCCAGAGGCAGUGGGAUCCCUGAGUGCUGAAUGCUCGCCUGCAGAGCAGCCCAGAAAGAGCCCUGACUGGGGAGAGAACAUUUUAGAAUCUCUAGUGUAAAAGACAUCAACGUGCUUAGCCUUUAUUUCAGAAAAAAAUCAGGGUGGUUCCCAGCUCCCCAGUCCAGGACAACCAUUAGUCCUGAUGAGUGAGCUGACGCUGGUGCUGGAACCUGCUGGCACCUCACUGGCCACAUCUUUGGAAGGGGAUGGUGGCCUUGCAUCCAAGAUGCCUGAAAAUCAGCACGUGCAGGGCCUCCCUAUCCAGCCAGCAUUUUCCUUCCAGCUGAGGCAGGUGAAGACUUCAUAAGCUCAUCACAGGGGAGGGAAUUAGGAGCAGGGCAGCAGGUAAUUAAACAAGAUAAAUUAUACCUGAUUUCCAACACCAGCUACAAAGAGUUGAAGAUGAUACCUAUGGGUCGCGUUAACACAGGGGGCAACUGCCUUGAUCGGCCUGCCAUGGGUCAUCAGACUGCUUCCUAAAUUGAGAGAAACUGAGCAAUCUCUCAGCCACUGCUAUAGUCUAACUUCUUGUUUGCUGAGUAAUUGUUUCUAAUGUCUCUGAACUCAAAGUGAGGUGCUCCAAGACGCUGUGAACUUCUGCAAAGACACCUCCUUACCUACUGGGAUCACGUGACCUGACCUCACUCCCAGCCAGGCUCCCAAAGGGCUCAUUCCAGCCAUUCCAAUCUCUUCUUCUUUAUGCAAACACUUUUCCCCCACAACAAGCCUUGUUUGUUCCGAUAGGAAUACGUGUACGUCAGUGCACUUGUCCUUACGUCAGUUCCUUACACCACCAAAGCACUUCACCUUUCUGGAAAUAAAACUUUUAAGACACUACUAUAAGUAAAAAUGAGAGUAUUCACUAGACUUAUUGCUCAGGCACAUUUGAGUGGGUCCCAGCUGUGUGAUUAAGAAGUCAACUGGGUGGCCUUUUCUGGGUUAUCUUCUGAUCAUGGCCUUUCAACCCAACAAGGGCCCUUCCCUGCUCUUCCACCAGUAAAGGCUCCUGGCCUCUCAUCAGGAUCUGCCCCCCAGAGACCCCCCCCAGACACUGCAGGGCCUGGUGAUGCUGUCCUCUGUACCGGAAAUGGCAGGCACUGUCAGAUUUCCACUCUUCUGCCUUUAGGAAGGCUGGGUGCUUCUUGCUCUGACAGCCAGUCUGGGGAGAUGACUCUUACGUUGCUUGAGUCUUGGUGGCAGGCUGCUGUCCACGGGGGAGAAGUCUCUGCUCUGGACUGGACAGAAGAGAGACUUUUACCCUGGGGCACUCACACGGCCAAGCUUCUGCCACCACUUCAUUAGCUGUAUUCUCCAUAGUAUGGUGAAAUAGCAGGUGCGUCUUCUAGUUUAUUCCUCCUGGGGACAUUUCCUCAAAGCAGUUUUGCGCCCCCGCAAGGGAAUGGUCAGCCUAAGGGUAAUGUACAGCCCGUGCUUGGAGAACCAUGGAAGCUACACCCCUACAGGUGCAUACUGUUCUGCUUUUCCAAUAAAUACGAGCGGCGAUUUCAACCACAA